CUUGGGUGGUCCCUUCAGCCUUUCCUUCCAGGGGAGGGACUGACUGCUCGUGCUAGGAGGCCAGACGAGGGUGGGCAUAAACUGGGGAACCCUAUGGCUUCUCUUCCCCUCCCGGAUCAGAGAAAAGGGUGCCGCUAAGGCUGGAGGUUGUAGAAAUCCAACUGGGUCCCCAGACUUCCAUUUCUGUGGGCAAGGUACUCUGGUUCCAAACCCAUGCACAAGUUGCUGUUCUCAUAGCAACGCUAAUCCCUGUGCCUGAGGGCACUUCCGCCUUGCCUGGGUGCUGGUUGUGUUGGGGCAUGGGAGACAGGUGCACCUGCAGAAGGAAUUUGCCUGCUUCUCAUGCCACCACACCCAUUUAACAUUUCAUGCCCCAAAUCCCUGGUGUGGUCAGGCAGAUCCCCAAGGAGCCUGAAUCACCCCCCUACCCGACAGUAAUUUCACUGCUACAGUCAAACACAUCCUUCUCCUCCAUGCUGGCCUGUGGUUCACUGGGGGUUGGGGAGUGUUCAGGUGGAGAGCAGAUUGACAGUGCCCCUACCAGUAGAUGAGCUUGGAACUGCCCCUUGAGGGUCAGUCACAAACCAGUCCAGCCUACUUCCUCCCAUUGCACCAUGGGCAUCUGGCCUCCCAGGAAGUGGGGCAGGAAGCGUGGUCAUGAGAUGGAGAUAAGGUGGGAGGUAGAAGUCUCUCUUUUCUGGAGCUCCCUCCCAUCCUGACCCAGCAAUCUCUCCUUGCUCUCACAGUCCAUCAGCUCCUUGCUCAGAGGGUUCUCUAUUUCCAGCCACUAUGAGUUUGGAGGCUUUACCUUACUAGUUCCCCAGAUGCCGGAAACAGAAAUGUCCACAAGAAAUUGCUCUAUUUACUCUGUCCAGCUGGCUGGCUAAAAGCCAGAUGGCAUCUGUCAGUUUACACCUUGAACCCACCUCUUCAUCCAACUCUCCCUGUACCUUGUCCCUCGGUCAGAAGCAACUCCCCAGGAUAGCUGACUCAACUGGACAUUGGCCUCCCUUGCAGAGGGUGGGGAGAUUGAGGUUUCAAGCAUCCAUCUCCCCAUCUUCCUUGGCCUAGCCUUUGAAUGAGACAGCUACCAGAGCAAAGGAGUUGGCUUCCCCUGGUUUGCCAAGCAAAUGAACCCUAUGGAUUUGUUUCCUCCAUCUCAAGACCCAAGGAAGAGUUGCCAGCCAAUUCUGUGCCCCUUCCUCAAUUCUGUGUCCGCACUGCUCUCCAGGUGGGGCUGCGAGCUCCAUCCAAAUCGCCUUUGAGGAGGUGCCCCAACUCCCACCCAGAGCCAGCAUCAGUCAUGUGACCUGCGUAGACCAAUCUGAGCAUACCAUGGUGCUGCGUUGCCAGCUCUCUGCUGAGGAGGUGCGGUUCCCAGUCUCUGUGACCCAGCAGUCCCCCGCUGCCGUCUCCAUGGAGACCUACCACGUCACUCUGACACUGCCACCAACACAGUUGGAAGUCAACCUGGAGGAAAUCCCUGGUGAGGGGCUGCUCAUAUCCUGGGCCUUCACUGAUCGCCCAGAUCUCAGCCUAACGGUGCUUCCCAAGCUUCAGGCCAGGGAGAGAGGUGAAGAACAAGUGGAGCUCUCCACAAUUGAGGAACUGAUCAAGGAUGCCAUAGUCAGCACCCAGCCAGCCAUGAUGGUCAACCUCAGGGCUUGCUCUGCCCCAGGAGGCCUGGUACCCAGUGAGAAGCCACCCAUGAUGCCCCAGGCUCAGCCAGCCAUCCCCAGACCUAACCGGUUAUUCCUACGGCAGCUUCGGGCAUCUCACUUGGGAAAUGAGCUGGAAGGCACCGAGGAACUGUGCUGUGUAGCUGAACUCGACAACCCCAUGCAGCAGAAGUGGACCAAGCCCGCGAGGGCUGGAUCCGAGGUGGAGUGGACAGAAGACCUGGCACUGGAUCUGGGCCCCCAGAGCCGGGAGCUGACCCUCAAAGUGCUGAGGAGCAGCAGCUGUGGAGACACCGAACUCCUAGGCCAGGCCACACUGCCUGUGGGCUCCCCCUCCAGACCACUGUCUCGAAGACAGUUGUGCCCACUCACCCCAGGGCCAGGGAAAGCCCUGGGACCAGCAGCCACCAUGGCAGUGGAGCUUCACUAUGAGGAGGGCUCUCCCCGGAACCUGGGUACUCCCACCUCCUCCACUCCACGCCCCAGCAUCACACCUACCAAGAAGAUUGAGCUUGACCGGACCAUCAUGCCCGAUGGCACCAUUGUCACCACAGUCACCACUGUCCAGUCCCGGCCCCGUAUAGACGGCAAAUUAGACUCCCCCUCCCGCUCCCCGUCCAAGGUGGAGGUGACCGAGAAGACGACAACUGUGCUGAGUGAGAGCAGUGGCCCCAGCAAUACCUCCCAUAGCAGCAGCCCAGGGGACAGCCACCUUUCCAACGGCUUGGACCCUGUAGCAGAGACAGCGAUUCGCCAGCUGACAGAGCCCAGUGGGCGGGUGGCCAAGAAGACACCCACCAAGCGCAGCACUCUCAUCAUCUCUGGUGUUUCCAAGGUGCCCAUUGCUCAGGACGAGUUGGCGCUAUCCCUGGGCUAUGCGGCAUCCCUGGAAGCCUCAGUGCAGGAUGAUGCAGGGACCAGCGGAGGCCCCUCUUCACCUCCCUCAGACCCACCAGCCAUGUCUCCAGGACCGCUAGAUGCCCUCUCUAGUCCCACAAGUGUCCAGGAAGCAGACGAGACAACCCGUUCGGAUAUUUCUGAGAGGCCAUCUGUGGAUGAUAUUGAGUCGGAAACGGGGUCCACUGGUGCCCUGGAGACCCGCAGCCUCAAGGAUCACAAAGUGAGUUUCCUGCGCAGCGGCACUAAGCUCAUCUUCCGCCGGAGGCCUAGGCAGAAGGAAGCUGGCCUGAGCCAAUCACACGAUGACCUCUCCAACGCAACGGCCACGCCCAGUGUCCGAAAGAAGGCCGGCAGCUUUUCUCGCCGCCUUAUCAAGCGCUUUUCCUUCAAAUCCAAACCCAAGGCCAAUGGUAACCCCAGCCCCCAGCUCUGAGGACCCAGCUCUGAAAGGGCACGAGUUCUCUCAGCCCAUUCCCCACCUCCCCUUCCAUACCCCUUCCUGGAUCUCCAGUGCCUGGGCCAGGAAAGCCCUCUGGGUUCCGGGAAGCCCCGUCCACCCUGGGCCAUGGGGCCGGUUGGAAGGAUACUUGGAACGGGAAGCACAUGAGAGGUGGGCACCCGGUGCCGAGGACAUGGACGAGGGACUGGUGGCUGGGAGGGAGAGGAGGGCCCUGUCCGGCAUGUGUGGGUAUUCCCCAGAAGCAUUUGCCUCCUGCUGAGCCUGGUCCCUGAGCGGAGUCCCAGGGUGCUCAGCUCUUCAGCUGACCCUUCUUCCCUUAUUUAUUCUCUUUUCUAUUUAUAUGUGUGGCUUAGGACCCUCCGUGAACAGAUGAUAGAGGGCAUCUCUCCCAGGUGACCCUUCUUUUCUGUCCCAGGAGGGUGGGUAAUUCCCUUUGGGAUGGGGCUCCCACACCUCCCUCAGGUCCCCACUCAGACCAGCACCAGUGUCUGCCUCUGAGAAUGUUGGCAGCUCACAGAGAGCAGGGCCGGCCCGGGAUGGGGGGCAGGUACUCCCCACCUUCCUGCCUCCCCUCCUGCUCCUCAUCCCUCCCUCCCCCUUUAUUACCGUUUUUUGUACUUGAUGCCUUCUCUGUGAGCAGUGGCUCUGUGGGAAGGAGGGAGCCGGGAGCCUGGUGGGAAGCCUUCCCCAGAGAGAUGGCUUUAGGGGCUUUAUUUAAAGACUGUGAUGAUGGAGCCACGCAAGGCUGCACCUCUGUGUGUUGGGAGACGAUGAUGAUGUCCAUUGCUGUGUGAUGGCUUGGAAUUUAAUUUAUUAAAGUCAAAUUGGAGUUUAUAAACUGGACAACUGGUUAUCCUUUGAAAGGCAGUAGGCAGCCAGGCUGUGACAUGGAUGGUGUGGGAGGAUGAGACAGGGGCCCGGAUAAUGAGGUUGGGUAGAUGACACACAUUGUGGAUCUGCUAAGAAGUUCCUGCAGGGAAGAAGGGGUGUGCAGAGAAAGGAUGGAAGAGACAGGAGGCUCUGGAGUAUGAAAUUGUAGCAAAAAACUCAAUCAACUAGUACAGGUUAGUCUUCAUUCCCCUUUCUGGAACAGGCUGCUCCUUCUAGGAUGUAAUGGAGAUCAAAGCUUGGACCCUGUAACUAGACUGCCUGCCUGGGUUUGAGUCCCAGCUCUUCUAAUUACUUGUGUGACCUUGGGCAAGUUAUGUAACCUCUAAGUGCCUCAGUUUUCUCAUCUGUAAAAUGGGAACUUCAAUCAUCAUGGCUAUCAUUUGGUUGUGGAUGAGAAGUAAAUGAAGUGCUGAGUGUUAACUGUUGCCUCAGAAGAAACUGGGAGGGGGAAGUCUUAGAAGUGUUUCAACAUAAUAAAAGCUCUCUCAUUCUGAAAUGUGGGCAAAUUUCAGGGAUUGAUAGAUCCUAGCAAACUGUGUCCCUGGUUCCCGUGCUUGAGAUCUUAUACAGGACUUGAACCAGGUAAGCUGCUACAGGAUAUUGGGCAGAAUGCAGGACCAGGAAGCAAGAAAACUGAGUCUGCCACAGACAAACCAAGUGAUCUUGAGCAGGCAACUUCUCCUUUGGGGACCUCAGUUUCCUCAUAUCUAAAAUAAGGGUGACCUGGAUAAACAUUCAGGUCACUUCCAGCCUUGACAUUCUAUGACUACCUAUAUCUCAGGGUGUUUAGGGCACAUGCCUUUGGGUAGAUAGCAUGUGGAAAUUGUUACUAUUCCCCAUGCUCCUGUCCACACUACUCACCAAAUAUGAGAUAUCCGGGAAGAAUGGAGGGUAUAGAUUUUUUUUUUCAAUUAGAUAAUUUAGUUUUAUAUAUUUGGGGGGACAAGUGCAGGUUUCUUACAUGCAUAUAUUGCAUGCAUAGAGGUGAAGUCUGGGCUUUUUUUAGUGUGCGCAUCGCCCAAAUAGUGAACAUCAUACCCAAUAGGUAGUUUUUCAACCCUCACCCUCCUCCCACCUUCUCACCUUUCAUAGUCUCCGAUGUCUUUUAUUCCACUCUAUAUGUCCAUGUAUACCCAUUAUUUAGCUCCCACUUAUAAAUGAGAAUAUGCCAUAUUUGACUUUGUUUCUGAGUUAUUUCACCGAGGAUAAUGGCCUCCAGUUCCACCCAUGUUGCUGGAAAACACAUGAUUUCAUUCUUUUUUAUGGCUGAGUAGUAUUCCACUGUGUGUGUGUGUGUUGGGCGAUGAUAAUGAUGUCCAUUGCUGUGUGACAGCUUGGAAUUUAAUUUAUUAAAGUCAAGUUGGAGUUUA